AGCACUUCCGGUCACGCCAUCGUUGCUGCCUUCUUCGUCAAGUUUCUAAAGGCCACCUACCUUCCUUGGCUCCUGCUCCCUUUCUCCAUCUUCAGACAUAACAGCAAAGCAUUUUCAGCUCUCUGACUCUGACCUGCUCCCGUUGCCAUCUCUCCUCUGACUCUGAUCCUCCUGCCUCCUUAUAAGGAUCCCAGUAAUUACACUGGGCUCACCAAGAUAAUCCAGGAUAAUCUCUUCAUCUCAGAAUCUUAACUCAGUCACAUCUGCAAAGCCCAUUUGCCAUGUAAGGUAACAUCUUCACAAGGGUUGGGAUUUGAACAUCUUGGGAGGACCAUUAUUCUGCUUACCACACCAGGUUAAUGAAUUACCAAGUAAAAUACCUAAUUAGAAUUACACAUCUCUUUUGUAGGUUAUUUUCACUGAAACAGGCAUUAAUUUCUAAAGUUGUAGGAGUCAUAAAAUGGCUUUAUUUAGACAAUACUUCCAAGGAAAGAUUUGUAUUAACAGAGAAUAGAACUAGUUGGUAACAGUUACAAAUAUUCUCAAAUCACCAUAUUGCAAAGGGGAACAAGAUUUACAUUCUUGUUAAAGUUCUCAAUUUAAUGCCUUUUUAAAUUCAGAUUAUUUGAAAUUAUUGUGCAGCAAAAUGGUUUCCACGCCUCCACAGCAGCAGGGGAGCGGGCACAGAGCCUUCAUAUCUUUCUGAGUUUCCUUUUGUUAAUUCUGAAGAUUUGCAUUUGUAAAGCUAGGCUCUGGAAUUUCUUAGCUAGUUUUAAAUAAAAAACAUGUCUGGGUCCUCGUUAUGCUGGCAGAAAUGGAGAAAAAGCUGAAAGGAUUUUAUUACCAAUGAAAUUCUAUAUUUUGUGCCUUGUAAAGUAGUUGUGAAGAUUUAAUGUGACCACUUACAAGCCCUGACUACUGCUUGAUGAAUGAGAGCAGUUUGAGUCUCUUACCUUCUUUUUUGUACUUUCCGCCCUUUUGUAUCUUCCUGCUGAGCUCAGAUAAUUUCGUCUUACCUGUCUUUAAAUUUAAAUUCUCUACUUAAUCUUCUAAUUAAAGCUAUCCCUUGAGUUUUUAAUUUUGAGUACUGUAUUUUUUUUCUAAAUGUUUGAUUAGGUUCAAUUAUGGUCUGCCAUUUGUUAUGGCUUCCUGUUGCUUGGUAAGAUCUUCAAGUUUUUUAUUUAUCUCUUUAUGCAUAGUAAACAUAGUCGUCUUAUAGUUUGUGUUUGAUAAUCCUAUUGUUUAAAGUCUUUUUGUGAACAUUUCUGUUGUCAGCUGAUCCUGCUGAUUUGCUUCUUUAUCUAAUUCAAGGCUCAAGGUUCCCAGGGCAAGUUAUGUGAUCCAAAUCUGAGCUGCAAAACUGGCCUGCUUCCAUUCACCCUCCCCUUUAGGGGGUAGCCCUUUGAGGUCCCAGCUCAUUGUUGGGAAUGUCUCCUCUUAGUUUUCCCACUUAGUGUAGCUCUGGGUUUUAAUCUCUUAUCUCUUUUGCCUUUCAAGGCAGCCAAAAUGAAAGCUGAAAUUUUUGGAAUAGACAAAUGCCCUUAGGACAGAAGUUGCUUCACUGCUCUAUUUACCUCUAGGUUCCCCAUUUCCCAGGAAUGUUGCCCUAGUGUUUCCAUACUGCCAUUUUAUUGUUUUUAAGUAGGUGUUACUACUUUUCUUUCAUCAAGAUUUUUAAAAUUUGUUUUCAACCUGAUGAUUGGUCCAAAUAAUGUGGCAGGCAAUCAUCAGAACUAGAAACAUUUCUUAUAACUCCUUGCUACAUUUUCUUUGAGAUUAGAUUUAGGCUCAGAACUUCAUUAUCUUUUGGGUUUUGUUUCUUCUGUUUUAUAGAGGACACAUCUGAUGCUCAGAAAAGUACAAAUACUUGCUCAAGGUCACAUAGCAAGUAAGUGGUAAUAUUGGGCUUUGAACCCAGCUCUGUCCAACCCUGAAACCUACACUGUGUCAGUUUUUGUUCCUGGGUUCUGGAACUUCUUUCUUUUAGGAAGCAGGUAAAUGACUCGUGAUUUUCUUCCUUGAGUUUUAUCUCUCAAGGUCAAGACCAUCUAUCUCCCUGUCUCUUGGAAGCACACACAGUUCUGUGCUUUUUUCACAAGGUCCUUGUCCUGUUUCUAAGACGUCCUGAUAAAUAAGUAUCCCUUUCUACCACCCACCUUGUACCUUUCAGAACUGAAUUCAGGGACAUUCAGUAUCCAACUGUAACCAUAAAGUUUGAUUUCCUUUUCAACUGCAGUAUUUUCCUCAAAAGACCUAGAUGAAUUCCCUGCUGAAUUUGGAAAGAGCUAAGGACAAAGUGACCCGGGAAGCAAUCCUUUUAGAUGAAAGGAGGAGGGAGAAUGAUACAAGUAGGGGUUAGAGAACUUACAGUUUAGUUGUAUAGUGGUGGGAUAGUUGAAGAUUUUGGAUUGGUGAAUGCCCACAAGGCACCUUGUCAUGGUGACAAAUACAGGAGCUUUGGAGCCAGACCCACUUCAGCUGAAUAUCAGUUCACCUACAUAUUAACUCUAAAAUGUUGGGCAAGUCAGCUUCCCUCUCUUGACCAUCAGUUUCUUCAUCCACAAACUUGGAAUAAUAAUAGCAAACUUUCAAGGUUUCCGUGUGAAAUACCAAUGAUGUAUUUCAGUGAAGUGUUUGUGUUUGGUGCAUGCUUACUAAAUGGUUGUGGUAGUUAUUAUUAUUGUUGUCCCCCUCAAACUUUUCAUCUGGUGGGUGCCCUAAGACCAGGCAGGAGAGUUCAUUUUUCAUUUGUGUGUAUGCCCAGUUACUCCUCUCUCCUCUGUUGCAUCAUCUUCUUCAGUCUCCUGAAGAUCUCUUACCGUCUACGUUCUUCCCAAUCCUUGCUUUCCUCUCCUAGUUCUACACAGUCAACACCUCCUUUGUUCAGAUAAUCUUCCCAUUUCCCUACUCAAUUUAAUCUCUUUUCAUUGCCUCUGCAUUGUCCUCCAGAUAAACCAGUCAUCCUCAUAUCACUUUGUUUCUUCAUGUCCCUCUCUCCCUGAUUUGGGAGGCCACCCCAAAGUGAGACAUAUCACUGGGUCUCAGCAGGCCUUAAUUUCUCAGCUGAUUCUCUGUCUUAUUUUGUCAGCUUCUUUUCAUUAAGUAAAAGUUAUGUUUUUCUGUGUAUUAUUUUUUAAGCUGUUUAGUUAUGGAUAUCUUCCUUUUUUACGUAUUUUACAUUAUAAAAGUAGAGACAUGCUCAUUUUGAAGAUUUUAGAGAACAACAAAACUUUAUUAGGAAGGAAAUAAAAGUGACCCACAGUUUUAUUAACUAGAGAUAAAUACUAUUCAGUAAUUGAUAUAUUUCUUUUCAGUAUAUACAGUUUUGUAUCAUUUGCUAGGACUGUGUACCACAGUCUGGGUGGCUUAAACAAUAGAAAUUUAUUUUUUCCCAAUUCUGGAGGCUAGACGUCUGAGAUCAAGGUGCUGGCAGGGUUGGUUUCUUCUCAGGCCUCUCUCCUUGGCAUGUAGAUGGCCGUCUUCUCCUUCCUGUGUCCUCACAUGGUUUUCCUUCUCUGUAUAUCUCUGUCUUUAUCUCCUCUUCUUUUUAUUUUAUUUUUGCAAUUCUCCUGCCUCAGUCUCCUGAGUAGCUGGGAUUGCAGGUGCCCACCACCAUGCCCGGCUAAUUUUUGUGUUUUUAGUAGAGACGGGUUUUCACCAUGUUGGCCAGGCUGGUCUCAAACUCCUGACCUCAAAUGAUCUGCCCGCCUCGGCCUCCCAAAGUGCUAGGAUUACAGGCAUGAGCCCCCGCACCGGGCUUAUCUCCUCUUCUUAUAAGGACACCAGGCAUGUUGGAUUAGAACUCUAAUGAUGUCAUUUUAAUUUAACUACCUAACUAGACACUAAUGAUGUCAUUUUUAAUUUAACUACCUUUUUAAAGAUCUUGUCUCCAGUGUAGUCACGUUCUGAGGUACUAGGGGUUGGGACUUCACCGUAUGAAUUUUGAGGGGACACAGUUCAGCCCAUAACACCUGCUUUCUUCUCUAAAAGUUAUCUUUUAAGAAUUCCCACUUGUCGAUAACAAUUCUUUGACAAUAGUUCUGAUGACUACAUAAUAUCCCAUCAUUAAAAUAUACCACAAUUUACUUAAUCAAUUUCAUAUUCUUGGACCUUUCAGGUGUUUUCAUUUUUUCACUAAUAUAAAUGCUUCCAUAAGUAGUUUUGUACAUGGAUGUUUGGAUAUCUGACUAUUUGUUUGGAAUAGAUUGCUUGAAGAGUGAUUAUUGGGUCAAAAGGUAUGACUAUUCUCUGGUUUUUAAUUACAUACUGCAAAAUUGUUUUCCAGAAAAUUGUACUAAUUUACAUUCAUACCAGGAAGGAGAAUAGUCAGUUAGGCAUUCAUAUAAGCUGCUGGUGGGAAUGAGAAAGGAAAAAUAAACUCUCAUGGUUGUUUCACUUUACAUUAAUUGAUGACUAACAAAAUGGAAUAUUUCAUGUAUUUAUUAAUCUGUUUGCAUUUCCUUUUUUGUGAACUGUUACUCAUGUUCUUUGCCCAUUUAUGUAUGUGAGUCUAUCAUUUUAGGUGAUAAGAUUAUGAUUUAGAGUGAGUUCUACUCUAAAGAGGGAAAUUUCAGAAAAAGUGAAAUUCCAAAGAAUGUUAUGGAUCCAGAAUCCAAGGACUAUUGGUCUGAGUCUCUUCUUUGGAGAAGACUUGGCAUGUGAUGACAUAUAGGUAAAGGAAUGGCUGCAGGAAAGCUUGGCAGGGAAGAGUUGAAUGUAUUCCUUACGCAGGGAAAUUUGUUACAGGCACAGUACUGCCACUUAUACUACUGAAGAGAAAGGCUGUGAGUGAAUUAACUGAGGAAAGGCAAGCUAGAUGCAUAUUAUAUAUGGGAAUCUUCUAGGAAAAAAAGCACAGAGAUAUGAUUCACAUGACCAUAACUCUUGCAAAGGUUUUAGAAUUUGUGAGACACUGGGGAGGUUCUCAUGGGGAAAAGUCUUAUGUAUGUGAUUAAUGUCAAAAAGCCCUUUGUCAGUGUUCAAGGGAGGUACCUCAGAGUACUCAUGAUAAAGAGAAACCCUAUGAAUGCUGUGAAUGUAGUGAAUAUAAAGAAAUUUUUAAUCAUGAUGCCAGUCUUACUUACCAUCUGAGGACUCACACCUGAGAAUUCAUUGAUUUGUUAUGGCCAUAAGAAUGUGGAAAGGCAGGACAUGAUUCUCUUUCAACACCAGAAAUUUCAUAGGGUAGAAAAACUUUCCCAAUGCUGGACAAAUUGCAGUGGGUGAUGAAGCUUUUUGAAUCAUGCAAAAGUUUAUACUGGACAGAAUCCCUAUGAGUGUACUGACUGUGGGAAAGGCCUCAAGACAAACUCAGACUGUUUUUUUUAACAUGAGAGAAUUCAUAGUGGAGAACAACCCUAUGCUCAUAAUGCAUGUGGAAAGGCUUUCAGAUCCAGCUCAGACUUUACUAAACAUGAGAGAAUUCAUAGUGGAAAGUAACCUUAUGCAAUGAUGAAUGUGGGAAAGGGUAUCUGGAGAUAACAGACCUUCAAAAACAUUAGAAAAUUUAUAGCGGAGAUGGAAAGAGAUCCUUUCAGUGUAAUGAAUAUGGAAAUGUUUUUAAUCUAGAGCUCAAAUUUUAUUUGUCAUCAAAGAUAAUCUUUUACAAUGAAUAUACAAAAACCUCCAAACAGAAAUCAAUCCUUGUUCAUCAUCUGCAGAUUCAUAGUGGACAGACACUCUGUACCUGUAAUGAAUAAGCCUUCAAUUAGAGGCUAAGUCUUAUUCAUUAUCAGAGGAUUCAUAAAGGCAUCACCUUCUAUGUACGUAAAAAAUUAUGGGUAUGCUUUCAGCAGGAUAUCAGCCUUAUUUGAUAUUGGCAAGUCUAUAGCGAGUUCGCUUAAAUGCAGUGAGUGUGGAAAGGCCUUCAAUCUGAAGUUUAAUCUUACUCAGCAUCAGAAAAUACAGAGUGGCAGGAAUCUUAUUAAUGUAAUGUGUGUGGGAAAGUCUUUAUGAGAAAAUCACGUCUUGGUAAAAAUGAAAAAAAGAUUCUUUGUAAAAGUUAAAAUAGUUACCACAUAAUUACACGCCUGCCAGUGUGCCAAGCACUACAAGAACUUUACAUUGUUUAAUCAUUUUUUUACAAUAAUCAUACAAUGUAGAAAUCCUCGUUGUUUUACACACACAUGAAGAAACCAAAGAAAUGAGGUGGAAAAACUUCCCCAAGAUCACAUACUAGUCACUGGAAGAGCCAGGGUUUGAGUCCUAGAGAGUUUAAUUGUUCUGGGUUUAUAGUGGCAAUAUGUAAAUCUUCAAGGAUGUGUUAGUCUUUAUUCAUUAUUAAGAAAUUCCUUCAGAAAUCAGGAUUCACUCUUCAGUGAGUAUUGGGAGCCUUCAGUCAGUUUUGGAAUUAGAGACUCUACAUUGGGUUCUAUCAAAUUUAGUAAGGACUAUAAAGACUUUAUCAUAUUUAUAUUAUCCCUUUGAAUAGGGAUUACUUCCAAUCUUGAAAGAUUUCAUUAAUAACAAAAUUCUGUUCUCAAAUGCUCACCCUAACCACUUUCUGUGGUGUAGACAACGUGGAGUGGGAUGGAAAGCACAGGCUCUGGGAUUGGCCAGGAUAGCUUCACCAUCAGGAACAAGGUAGAGUUACCCAGUUCUUAAAAAGAUUGAGUAGGAAUGGAGAGGACAGAUGUGGUGAGAGCUUCAGGAACAGAGUCAGGUCAUUCUAGGAAUUAUAACCAAACAAGCCAAAAUAAAGUAGAAUUCAGCCUAUAAGGAAGUGGAGAAGCUAGGGUAUGUGGCAUGAUUUUCUCCCCAGAUGGAUUUAGCUAUAGGUUGCUUGUGUAUCACCCAGUAUUCAGAGGAACUUGAAUUUGAAAUUGCUUCAGGAAUAUGCAGUACUCUAGCACUGAGUCAAAAAUAAGCGUGACUUUCAGAAACUCAAGGUAUAAGAAAUAUUAAUAAAUUGAUUUUCUACCUUCUCACUUCAAGGAGGCAGUGUGCUACACCAGAAAGUAUUCAGGAUCUACCUUCAGGUAUAACUGGGUUUAUUUGCCAGCUUAACCACCUUCUAGCUGUGUGACUUUAGUUAUAUUAAUAAAUCUCUUUGAGUCUCACCUUGCUCAUUUUUUUUUUAGGUCAGGAUAUAAUACUGUACCAAGUUGUAAGGAUUCUAGAUAAAGGGUAUAAAGUGUCUAGUAUGGCGCCUGGCAUGUAGUACAUACCUAAUAAAUAUGUUAUUGAAAUAUAUUAUUGUUGGUUCUGCAAGGAUCUUAACACUCUAUAAUAGACCUCUCCAACCCCAGUUGGGGAAUGAAUGUGUUACACUUGUGUUGUGAUAGUAUUAAUCACUUUAGAUUAUGGGGCUUCUGCUGGCUUAUAUGGUACCUUUGUGUGAAUUGUAAAAUAAUACCUCUUCCUCAAAAGACUUUCUUACCACUUGCUAGAAAAUUGUCAUAAUAAACACAGAUAUCUUUGAUGGUCAUAAUGUGAAUGGUAUUCUGCAGAAUCAUGCGGCCCACAAUUUGCAAAACCUGAAGUUGGUAGGCUGAAUAAAUGGCCCCCCAAAACUGUCUGCAUUUUAAUCUCUAGAACCUGUGAAUAUAUAUUACCUGAAAUGGUAAAAGGGACUUCGGCAGAUGUGAUCAAAUUAAGGAUUUUGAGAUGCAGGGAUAAUACUGGAUUAUUAGGGUGGGCCCAAUGUAAUCACAAGGAUCCUUAUAAGAGAGAGGCAGGAGGACCAGACUUAUAGAGAGAGAAUGUGAGGACUAAAGGAGAGGUCAGAGAGGGAAGAAGAUGCUAUGCUGCUGGCUUUGAAUUUGGAGAAAGGAGCCAUGAACAAAGAACUGCCUGGGAGGCAGAGGUUGCAGUGAGCUGAGAUCAUGCAACUGCACUCCAACCUGGGCAACAGAGUGAGAUUCUGUCUCAAAAAAGAAAGAAAGAAAGAAAGAUCCUGUGGGUAGGAGUGUGAUGGAUAGCCGGGUGCAUUGGCUCACAUCUGUAAUCCCAGCACUUUGGAAGGCCGAGGCGGGCAGAUCAUUUGAGGUCAGGAGUUCCAGACCAUCCUGGCCAACACUGUGAAACCCUGUCUCUACUACAAAUACAAAAUUAGCCAGGCAUGGUGGUGCACAUCUGUAGUCCCAGCUACUUGGGAGGCUGAGGCAGGAGAAUCGCUUGAACCUGGGAGGGGGAGGUUGCAGUGAGCUGAGAUCACGCCACUGCACUCCAGCCUGAGUGACAGAGUGAGACUCCGUCUCAAAAAGAAAAGAAAAAAAGGAGUGUGAUGGAUAGAUUGGAAAAGAGAACUGGGUGCAGGGAGACCAGUUAGGAGGCUAUUUAUAAAGUAGAUACUGAAAUCUGGGUUAAGGCAGUGGGAAUGAAAUGAGAAUACCAUAUAUGCAAUAAAUUUGGAACUUGGUCACUGACUAGAUAUAGGGGGACUGACGGAGAAGAAGGAAUCAAGGAUGAUGCCCAGUUGUCUUUCUGCCUUGGAUGGUUAACAAGUUGCAAAAACCAUUCAUGGAGAACUCAGAAUAAGGAGCAGGUUUGUGGGGAAAGAAUGACCUUUGCAGUGUCCAAGAGGAAUUAUUCAGUAGGUAGUCCGGAAUUCAUUCUGCUGCUGUGAAGCAAGUAGGGUUACAGAUAGAAAUCAGAUAGAAAUUUGGUAGUCAUCAAAUACAGAAGUGGUGGUUUUAAUUGAAGUAUCAAUGAGAUUGCCCCGGGAGAGGGUGGUGUGGAGUGAGAAAAAAAAAAGACCCAAGGCAGAAUCUCAGAAACCUAGGCAUUUUGAGGGAAGACAAAGCUGAGAAUCAGCAGAAGAAAGGUAGGAGGGGGACCAGAGGAGAUACAGCAUUCUUGUUCUGCCCUCUUGUGGCAAGCUGAGUGUGUCCCAGCAUAAAUCUUCCCUCUCUUGUCUUCAGUCUUCCAGGUCUCUGACUCAUAAUUCCAUUCCCACCCUACCUGGGAGAAUGGAGCUGCCAGGUCUUCUCAUGGUCAUUUCUCAAAUGUAAAGCUCCUCUUCGAUUAUUUCUACAAUUCAAGAGCAAUUUGGACCCCACCCCCAUGUUGCAAAAGAAUAAAAAGCAAACAGUGGGGCGGGGCUUCAGUUUCCACAUUUAUAUGCUCCACCAUCUUUUGAUCUAUUCUAUUGGCCUCAUUAAUUUUAGUACAUCUCAACUCUCAUCAUAUCCCUUCGCUCCCUUUAUAAUUAAAAGACAUUUUAUUUUGAAUUUUUUUAUUAUAGUAAAUAUACUGUAUAUUAUAGCAAGACCUAUGUAUGGCUUAAAAAAGAAAUAACAAAAAAUAGCAGUAUUAGCUUCACUUUUUUUCACCACCAGACUUGAACACUUGAAGGCUAGAAUGCAAAUUAGCCAACUUUGAAAUCUACUUCUUUUGGUUUUUAUCUAAAUACCAUUAUUUCAUGAGUUACCUAUUUCAGAUAUUAGCUGUUGACUUCCCAUUAUGGUAGAUGAAGAUUUAAUUCACUUUUUCUCCCUCAAUUACCUUCUCUAUUCUUUUAGUAUAGCUAUAGCAUACUUUCUGGUUAAUGAUGUUUAUACUAUUGUGAUUGUGCAAACAUUGUUCACUAAAGAGACAGGUAGUGAAUUGUGUCUAUGUUUCUGUUUUGAACACAUUUGUAUCAUUUCUAGAGUUAUAAUUCCCUUUUAUCUGUGUAUUUUUAUAUAUUUAUAUUUGAGGCAGAGUCUUGCCCUGUCACCCAGGCUAUAGUGCAAUAGUGCGAUCUUGGCUCACUGCAACCUCUGCCUCCUGGGUUCAAGCAAUUUUCCUGCCUCAGCCUCCAGGCAGCUGGGAUUACAGGCGCCCACCAUAUCUGGCUAAUUUUUUUGUAUUUUUAGUAGAGAUGGGGGUUCACCAUGUUGGCCAGGCUGGUUUCGAACUCCUGACCUCAAGUGAUCUGCUCGCCUUGGCCUCCCAAAAUAUCCUUAUUUUUUCUGUUAGCUCUAUCAUAUGUCUAUUUUUGUGUAACUGCUAAAAAACGUCAGAGUAUUCAGAAUAUUUAUUUUCUAGAAAUCCCCUUUGUAGAGCCUUCUCUCUUGAUCCAGUCUGGGCUGUUUUCAAUCCUGAAAGCUUUUGGGAUUUCCACUUUAUCCCUAAUAUUCUAAACUUUCAUGAUGAUGUGUGGAUAUUUGUAUAUCUGUUGUCCUAGAUACCUGGUAGGUAGACUCUUUCAGUUUGUAUGUUUUUGUACUUGGACUCUGGAAAGUUUUAUUAUUUCUUGGAUACUUUGUGAGCUCCAUAAGGACACAUUUUUAUCUAUUUUAUUUAUUUCUGUUUUUCCAGUGCCUAAAAUAGUGCCUGAUACAUGAUAGACAUUUAUUUGUUGAAUGAAUUACUAUUUACAUUUAAAAUAAUAAAAAUGAAAUAAUGCCUCCAGACCCACCGACCAGGACAAGAAAUAGAACAUUAUCAGUACUUUAGUGCCCUAUCCAAUCACACCUUCCUGUCCGCCUCCACCUAGAGAUAAUACUACCCUGAUUUUUGUAUUAACAAUUUCUUUGGUUUUCGUAUAUUUUUAUCACUUGUAUAUAUGUUUUUAAACAACAUAUUGUUUAGUUUUGAAAAAAUGGAAAAGCGAACACAAACCUAGUUGUACGAGAAAAGGGUACUGUUGCCCCUGUUAGAUAGUCUCCCAGGAAAACAGAGGUUCUGCGUCAAAAACUGAUUUUAGCUUCUCUGAGAACUGUAAAGCCAUUUCUGGGAUAAUUAGUGAAUGAGGUCAUGAAAUUUACUGUUACUGAUGAAAGUCCUAUCUGUCUAAUUUAAUUUUUCUAUUGCAGGUGACAUUUUCUCUCUUUUCAGCUCUCAGAGUUAUAGUUGACAAAAAUUAUACGUAUUCAAGGUGUAUACAUAUUCAAAGUGAUAUUUUGAUAUAAAUAUACAUUGGGAAAUGAUUUCUACAGUCAAGCUAAUUAACAUAUCCAUCAACUCACAGUUACCUUUUUUGUGGGAAUACUUAAGAUCUACUCUCUUAAUGAAUUUCAAGUAUGUAAUACAUUAUUACUAACUAUAUUCACCAUGCUGUACAUUAGAUCUCCAGAACUUACUCAUCUUACAACCACAAGUUUGUAUCCUUUGACCAUCUCUCCACUUCCCCCACACACUGGCUGACCUUGGGUAACCACCCAUCCACUCUCUGUUUCUAUGAGUUCAACUUUUUAAAGAUUCAGCAUAUAAGUGAGAUGAUGCAGUAUUUGUCUUUCCGUGUUUGGCUUAUAUCACUUAGCAUAGUGUCCUCCAGGUUCAUCUGUGUUGUUGCAAAUGGCAGGAUUUCCUUUAUCAAGGGUGAACAAUAUUCCAUUGUGUGUGUGUAUGUAUGUGUGUGUGUGUAUACACACAAUUUCUUAAUGCAUCUGUUGCAGACACUUAGAUUGUUUUCAUAUUGUAACUAUUGCUAAAAAUGCAGCAAUGAACAGGGGAGUUCAGAUGCUUCUUUAAGAUAGUGAUUUUAUCUCCUUUGGAUAUACACCCAGAAGUGGAAUUGCUGGAUCAUAUGUUCAAUUCUUAAUUUUGGGGGGGAACCUCCAUACUGUUUCUGCUAGUGACUGUACCACUUUAUACUCUCACCAACAAUGUAUAAAGGUUCACUUUUUGCCACUUUUUGCCAACACUUGUUAUCAUUUGACUUUUUGAUAAUAACUAUCAUAACAAGUGUGAGAUGUUAUCUCAUUGUGGUUUUAAUUUGCAUUUCCUUGAAGAUUAGAAAUGUUUAACACUUUCAAUAUACCUGUUGGGCAUUUGUAUGUCUUCCUUGGAAAAAAUGUCUAUUCAGGUCCUUUGCCCAUUUUUAAAUUGGGUUAUUUGUGUGUGUUUUUUUUUAACUACUGAGUUAACUAUGUGAGUUCCUUAUAUAUUUUGUAUAUUAACCCCUUAUCAGAUAUAUGGUUUGUGUAUAUUUUCUCCUAAUCUGUGGGUUGCCUUUUCAUUUUGUUGAUUGUUUCCCUUGCUGUGUAGAAACUUUGUAGUUUGAUGUAGUCCCACUUGUUUAUGUUUGCUUUUGUUACCUGCCUUUUUGGUGUAAUAACAAAAAAAUCAUUGUCAUGUUCAAUGUGAAGGACCUUUUCCGAUGUUUUCUUCUAGAAGUUGUAUGUUUUAGGACUUGCAUUUAAAUCUCUAAUCCAAUUUCCAAUUUGAGUUGAGGGGUGUGAGAGAGAGAGAGAGAGAGUGUGUGUGUGUGUGUGUGUGUGUGUAAGAUAAUGAUCCAAUUUCAUUUUUUUCUGCAAUGGACAUUCAGUUUUUCCAACACCAUUUGUUGAAGAAACUAUCCUUUCCACAUUAUGUAUUCUUGAUGCCUUUGUCAAAGAUUAGUUGACUGUAUAUGCAUGGAUUUGUUUCUGGGCUAUUUUAUUUAUUUGUCUAUGUGUCUGUUUUUAUGCCAGUACCAUGUUGUUUUGAUUACUAUAGCUUUGUAACGUAAUGUGAAAUCAGGAAGUAUGAUGCCUCUGACUUUGUUCUUCUUAUUCAAGAUUGCUUUUAGUUAUUAAUAGGGGUUUUAUUGAAUCUGCAGAUUGCUUUAGUUAGUACGGACAUUUUGACAAUAUUGAUUCUUCCAAUCCAUGAACACAGAAUACUUUUCAAUUUAUUUGUGUCUUUUUCAAUUUCUUCCAUUAUUGUUUUGUAGUUUUCAGUGUACAGAUCUUUUACCUCCUUGGUUAAAUUUAUUCCUAAGUAUUUUAUUGGUUUUGAUGUUAUUAUAAAUGGGAUUAUUUUCUUAAUUUCCCUUUUGGAUUAUUUAUUGUUAGUACAUAGAAAUAUUAUUGAUUUUUCUAUGCUGAUAGUAUAUUAUGUAACUUAAUUCAUUUAUUAGUUCUAAUAGUUUGUUUUAUGGAGUCCUUAGGUUUUUCUGUAUAUACGAUUAUGUCAUCUGCAAACAGAUAUAAUUUCACUUCUUCCUUUCCAAUUUGGAUGCAUUUUAUUUCCUUUUCUUGACUAAUUGCUCUGGUUAGGGCCUCCAGUACUAUGAUGAAUAGAAAUGGUGAGAGUGGGCAUCCUUGUCUUGUUCAUGAUCUUAGAGGAAAAGCUUACAACUUUUCAACAUUGAGUAUGUUGUUAGCCAUGGGCUUGUGAUAUACGGCCUUUACUGCCUUUGGGUACAUUCCUCUUAUACCUAAUUUGUUGAGAGUUUUUAUCAUUGAAGAUUUCUAAAUUUUGUUUCUCUUUCUCUUUAAGAUUGUAAUUUUUUUUCUUGUUUCCUUGAAUUCAAGAAUUUAAUCAGGGUAUCCUGAGUAUAUCUUAGAAUGUAAGCUCCACAAAGACAGGGAUUUUUGUCUGUUUUGUUCACUGAUAUAUCCCAAGUGCCUAGAAUAAUGCUGGCUAUGUAAUAAGUCCUCAUUAGAUGAGUUGAUUAAAUUAAUGUAUGAAUGCAUAAAUUGAUGAAUGGAUGGAUGAACAGGUACUCAAUCUUGUCUGGAAUUCAGGUAGCCCUUUCUUUAGCUCAGGGAAAUUUUCUUCUAUCAUUUAGUUAAAUAUUGCCUUUCUUCCUUCUAUUUCUUUUCUCCUUUAACUCCCCAUCCAUCUCCCAUAUUCACAUUUUAGGUUCAUUGACACUAUCCUCUAGAUACCUUGUCUUGUAUCUCAUUGUAUCUAUUGCUUUUUGGGUUUUUUUGCUCAGUGCCUUGAUAUAAAUCUUGCACUUAAUUUUCUAGUCAAGUAAUUCAGGGCUCAUCAUUGACAUCAUUUUUCAUUUUAUUGUUUAAUUGGAAUUUGAUACAGUUUGGAUUUGUGUCCCCACCUAAAUCUCAUGUUGAAUUGUGAUCCCUAAUUUGGGAGAGAGGCCUGGUGGGAGGUAAUUGGAUCAAGAGGGCAGAUUUCCCCCUUGCUGUUCUCAUGAUAGUGAGUUCUCACGAGAUCUGGUUGUUUAAAAGUGUGUAGCACCUCCACCCUUCUCUCUCUUCCUCCUGCUCUGGCCAUGUAAGAUGUGCCUGCUUCACUUUCACCUUCUGCCAUGAUUGUGAGUUUCCUGAGGCCUCCCCAGCCAAGCUUCCUAUACAGCCUGUGGAACCAUAAACUAAUUAAACCUCUUUUCUUUAUAAAUUAUGCAGUCUCAGGAAUUUCCUUAUAGCAGUGUGAGAACAGACUAAUAUAGAAUUUGUUUUUAAAGCUUUGAGCUCUAGAAAGUUUUUGUGUGUAUAUGCUGCAUUUUCCUCAGGUGUUCUUAUUACUUUUUAGUCAGUUUUUACAUAUCUUGUCUAAUAGCUUUGUUUUAUUUCUCUCUGACUGCUGAAACUUUUUAAUGUUUGUUUUUAUGAAUGAUCACUUUGUGGGCCUUGAUGUAGAUUGGAAUGUAUUUGAGUCAGUACUGCUAGAAUAUCAACUAUGUGCAGAUAUGAAUGGUGUUACUAUGGAAACGAGGUCACAUGUGAGUUCUGAUCUUCACACUGCCUUAUUUCCAGCGAAAAGUUGCCAUUUCUUUAGAACACUGAUUGUCCCCGGAUAAAACUGUGAACAUUCCAAUAUUUAGGCCUAGUCACCUUGGACACAAAUUGCACUCUGAAAUAUUGUUCUUUCACUGAGAGCAGACAAGCACAGUAUUUAAGUUUAUAUGCAAGGUCUCAAAAGCUAACACAAAGCUAGCUAGCAAAAAGAAAAAAGAAAGAGCUAAAAUGACUGUUAGAUGUAAUUCUACAUAACCUGUUUUUAACAAGAGCAUUCUAUAAGACUAAAUUCUAAAUUUUUUCAUCAAAGGGUGUUUUUCUACUCCUGAUUAAUUUUCACCUACUGUACCAUGGUAACUCUACCCAUUCAGAAUUUGAAUUCCUAGUUCAGGGAAAGGAGGAAUCUGGGGUAGUGGCAAUGCAAUAUCCUUGUUUAGACUUGAUGUUAAUUUGUAUCAGUGUUUGCUGGUAAUGCUAAUCAAAAACAAACUCCACCUAGAAACCUGUUAGUGGUAAAACAUGGAUAACACCAGUAAAGAGAAUUUAUAUGAUUUCAUUGAUCCAUUGUGUGGAGCUGUGAGGGAUCAAUAAAUAACAUUCAUCUUUCCUGACUAGGUUCAGAACCAAUUGAAAUUGAAAGAUGUAGGAAUCCGAUAAAUGGAACUCAAAACAUCAUCUUUAUUACUGAUAACACUUCAGAGAAUAUGGCUUUAAUGUGGACUUCCUAAUAUUGGACCCCAGAAUUAAGCAGAUUUACCUAAACCACCAUAAGCAAUGGUGAAAAACCACAAGACUCUGGGCCAAAAGUGGGCCACUUGAUGCAUGAUAUGUUUUCUGUAAGCAUGUAGAUGAAGGGCAGAGAGCAAGAGCCUAAGCCAAGCUGUAUUAGUCAGGGUUCUCUAGAGGGACAGAACUAUAUAUACACAUAAAAAUAAAGGGGAGCUUAUUAAGUAUUAACUUACACGAUCACAAGGUCUCACAAUAGGCUAUCGGCAAGCUGAGGAGCAAGAAGAGCCAAUCCGAGUCCCAAAACUGAAGAACUUGGAGUCUGAUGUUCAAGGGCAGGAAGCAUCCAGCACGAGAGAAAGAUGUAGGCUGGGAGGCUAGGUCAGUCUCUCCUUCUCACGUUUUUCUGCCUGCUUUAUAUUCGCUGGCAGCUGAUUAGAUUGUGCCCACCAGUUGAAGGGUAUAUCUGCCUUCCCCAGCCCGCUGACUCAAAUGUUAAUCUCUUUUGGCAACACCCUCACAGACACACCCAGGAUCAAUACUUUGUAUCCUUCAAUUCAAUCAAGUUGAUACUCAGUAUUAACCAUCACACAAGCAUACUCAGAUGUUUCUUCCAAACAUACUAGUCACAUAACUCAUUCCUUCUUCUGUGGACAGAAAAGCAGGAGUGUUAGUCUAUUUGAAGUUCUUCCACUUAGAAACAUGAGAAGUAAAGAUUAAGUGUUCCCUCUAACAUAGCUCAGUGAUGUAUUCAGUAUUGCCAUGUGCUUGAACUUGUCUAUCUCUUCAGGACCAAAAAUAUCAUAAUUUUGCUGUGACACGAAAGGUAUUAGGAUAUUUUAGGAAGACUGUAGUACAAAUAGCUCAAUUACAGAAUAUCAUGUUAAUGACAUAUCAAUAGAAUAUUUAAAACUCCAUCUAAAUGCUAUAACAAAACAUGAAGAAAUGCUUCUUAAAGGCAGAUGUACCAAAAGGAAUCCAUUCACCACUCUCUACCAAUGGGAACAUCAAACAUUGUACCUUUAGAGCAUGGUAUAUUUCUCCACUUAACACCUACUAGAACUCUGCAGUGAGGCUUCAAGUGAGAAACUUCUCUGUUAUAUCUGGGUUGAUGUAAGAUCCACAUAUCAGGAAAGUAAGUGUGUGUGUGUGUUUGUGUGUGUGUGUGUAUGAGAGAAUAAGAUAGGAGUGGGGGACAAGAAGGGAGAGGAGAGGAAAUAAAAGAAGGAAAAUGAGAUAUCAGGGAAUGAGCACCACAAGUGUAAAAUCCUAAGUGAUGUGGGUCAUGUGUUUGAUGGAGAGAUAGGGAGAGAGUAUUGUGUGGUAGUGGGGUAGUGGAGGUAUGUGGCCAAGGUAUGUGUGAUAAUGGUGUCAAUGGGGACAGUGUAAGGAUGGUAUGAAAUCACUGUGAUCAUGAAGACAGAGGCAAUGUGAGUGACAGUAACAGGAAGAGAUCAGAAUGUAUGUGACAGUUGUAGUUAUGGUCACAGUGUAUGUGAAAGACAAGAAUUGUGCAUGUGUGUGAAUAUGGUUGUGUGAGAAAGUGGGGAGGGAGAGGACAGGAUAAUGGGACACUGGGAUCAUUGUGUGUGUGAAAAUGUGGAUGGGACAUGUUGAUGUAGAGGGAGGUUGGAAUGGGGCAGGUGUAAUGUCAUUAUGGAAGAUAGGUACAUGAUGGAAGUGAGAAGGCUGGUGUAUGUCUGUGUGUCUAUGUGUGCUGGGGAAAAUGAGAAGUGUGUCUCUUUGUGAGGACAGAUGGAUACAGUGAGCAUGGGUAAUCACAGUCAAUGAAAAUGUGAUAAUUUGGAGUGGGAAAAUCAUGAGUGUCUGAAUAGGGUUGUUGAAUAAAGUAUAUGAUGGGAAAAUGCAAAGAGUUUCUGAGUGCCAGUGAGGAAUGGGGAAUAUAUGUGAGUGAGAGCAGAGUUGAUGUGGUUAUUGGUUGUGAGUAUGUAUGAAAUGGAGGUGGUAUGAGAAUGUGUGGAAGGAGAUUUGGAGGAUGAUACAAGUUUGAUAAUGGAGAUGUGGACUGUGUGUAUGAUAGUGGGUGUGGCUAGACACUGCGUAAUGGUGUAGUGUAGGGAUUGAGUAAUUGGGGUGUGACUAUAUGAAUGAUGGGGAUGGUGUGUAUGAUAAUGGGGAUUGAUUUAAGUUAGUGGUAUUUGACAGUGGGUGUCGUGGGUACCAUAUCUGUUCUGGUCUAAAGACAUUUUAUUUAUGAUAGUACAGGAUAGGACAGAGUAUGUGUGGAAAUGGGAGUGAUAGAGACAGUGUACAUGUUAGUGGGCAUAUUAAUCCAUUUUCACACUGCUAUAAAGAGAUACCUGAGACUGGACAAUUUAUUAAAAAGAAAGAGGGUUUAGGGUGCUGGUAUUGCAGGUGUGAACCACUGCCCUUGGCCUGGAAGAUCUCCAUUUUUAUGAUUUUUUUUCAUUUUUAAUUUUUUUUUAAGAGACAGGGUAUCCGCCGGGUGCGGUGGCUUAUGCCUGUGAUUCCAGCAGUUUGGGAGGCCGAGGCAGGCGAAUCGCUUGAGCUCAGGAGUUUGAGAUCAGCCUGGGCAACAUGGUAAAACCCUGUCUCUACAAAAAUAAUGCAAAAAUUAGACCGGUGUGGUGGCGGGUACCUGUGGUCCCAGUGCCUGGGAGGCUGAGGCGGGAGAAUUGCUUGAACCCAGGAGGCGGAGAUUGCAGUGAGCCGAGAUCGUGCCACUGAACUCCAGCCUGGGUGACAGAGUGAGACCCUGUCUCAAAAUGAAACAAAACAAAAAGAGACGGAGUCUUGCCCUGGCGCCCAGGCUGGGGUGCAGUGGUGCUAUCAUAGCUCACUGCAGCCUAAACUCCUGGGGUCAGGGGAUCCUUCUGCCUCAGCCUCCUGAGUAGCUGAGACUAGGAGGGUGAGCCACCGUGCUGGGCUAGGAUCUCCAUUUUUAGACACUUUAUCUCAGUGUAUUCAAAAUAUGGUUCUUGGACAAGUGUGGGUUGGUGAUCUGGUCUGCCAUGAACUGAGCCUAAGUGUUUGGCAAAUUUUACUGCAAUUUUAGAGUGAUUUUAUUUAUGUUGAAUCAAUAAUUUAAAAAGUGAGGCUUGUAUUUUGUAUUCUAUAAUUUACUGUAAUAUCAUUUUUUCUAGAAACAGACUCUUAUUUCACAAAAGUAUUGGUUGAAACGAAUUAAAGUGAACAAAAAACCAACUGGUUUUGCACAAGUAGUUUGAAAUAUAUUGCUCUAUCUUACUCAAAAUUGAUGCGUAUGUGAUUUCUUUUUCUAUAAUGUGAAGUUUUUUUUGUUGUUGUUCUUUGGGGAUCUUGUGCUCUACUCCUAAAAUAUUAAUGUCAUGCAGGAUUCCAGAAUUGUUUUGUUUUGUUCCAGAUAUUUGCCUUGCGUAUAUAAAGAUGUGGUCAUUCUUUGCAUGCUCUUUCCCCAGAGACACAUGUAAAUGGAGUUGUAAUUUCCUGUUGGUAAACAGCAAGUAUUUAAAUUUAGAAUCAGGUGGUAAGGUUGAUAUGUAGAAGGGUAAUACAUUGGAUUGCCUUCAAAGUGAUAUCUUUUCCAGUUAACUGUUAACUCACUAAUUUACUGUUUUUCUUUUCUUUCUUAUGCUUCAUGAAUUUAUGUGUCAUCUGUACAGGGGCCAUGUGCUAAUCUCUGCACGGUUCCAAUUUUAGUGUUUGUGCUGCCAAAGCAAGCACGGCUUUUCUUAAUCCUAUCAAAUAUUACAUGGUAUGUUAAAACAGUAUAGAUCUGGCUUAAGGUAUUUCAUGGAUGACAAAUGGACCUCAUGUUAUAGAGGAAUGAAAGAUAUAAAUUAAUAAAACAUGAUCAUGAUAAGAAUAAAACCAAACUAAAUCUCCUCUCCAGUGCUUGGCAGCACACUCCCGGAGAGGGUUCAGGCUGUAUGUGGCCCCCCAGCAGGUGCUCAGAGAUGGCUUAAUGGCCUCGGUGACAACAGGAGCCCAGACUGCAUAAGACUCUGCCUCUGCAGAUGCAGAACAGUAGGGGCCUCUGAUGUGCUUGAACAUCUGUUUUGGAUCUCCAUUUCUCCUCAAGAAGAGACUCCUUUUUAAAAAUUAUUUUUUUUGAAGCUGCAUUACUUACUGAUUUCCAGAGUCGUUUUACACCUGCCCUUCUCAAGGGAAUAUUUUGGGCAUAAUCUUUUUUUUUUUUUUAAUUAUACUAAGUUAUAGGGUACAUGUGCACAACGUGCAGGUUUGUUACUUAUGUAUACAUGUGCCAUGUUGGUGUGCUGCACCCAUUAACUCGUCAUUUACAUUAGGUAUAUCUCCUAAUGCUAUCCCUCCCCCCUUCCCCCACCCCACAACAGGCCCUGGUGUGUGAUGUUCCCCUUCCUGUGUCCAAGUGUUCUCAUUGUUCAGUUCCCACCUAUGAGUGAGAAUAUGCGGUGUUUGGUUUUUUGUCCUUGCAAUAGUUUGCUGAGAAUGAUGGUGUCCAGCUUCAUCCAUGUCCCUACAAAGGACAUGAACUCAUCAUUUUUUAUGGCUGCAUAGUAUUCCAUGGUGUAUAUGUGCCACAUUGUCUUAAUCCAGUCUAUCAUUGAUGGACAUUUGGGUUGGUUCCAAGUCUUUGCUAUUGUGAAUAGUGCCACAAUAAACAUACAUGUGCAUGUGUCUUUAUAGCAGCAUGAUUUAUGGAAUCCUUUGAGUAUAUACCUAGUAAUGGGAUGGCUGGGUCAAAUGGUAUUUCUAGUUCUAGAUCCCUGAGGAAUCGCCACACCGACUUCUACAGUGGUUGAACUAGUUUCCAGUGCCACCAACAGUGUAAAAGUGUUCCUAUUUCUCCACAUCCUCUCCAGCAUCUGUUGUUUCCUGACUUUUUAAUGAUUGCCAUUCUAACUGGUGUGAGAUGGUAUCUCAUUGUGGUUUUGAUUUGCAUUUCUCUGAUGGCCAGUGAUGAUGAGCAUUUUUUUAAUGUGUUUUUUGGCUGCAUAAAUGUCUUCCUUUGAAAAGUGUCUGUUCAUAUCCUUCGCCCACUUUUUGAUGGGGUUGUUUGUUUUUUUCUUGUAAAUUUGUUUGAGUUCAUUGUAGAUUCUGGAUAUUAGCCCUUUGUCAGAUGAGUAGGUUGCAAAAAUUUUCUCCCAUUCUGUAGGUUGCCUGUUCACUCUGGUGGUAGUUUCUUUUGCUGUGCAGAAGCUCUUUAGUUUAAUUAGAUCCCAUUUGUCAAUUUUGGCUUUUGUUGCCAUUGCUUUUGGUGUUUUAGACAUGAAGUCCUUGUUGGGCAUAAUCUUUUAAUCUUUCUGGAAAGCUAACAAAACAUUAUCUAUGCCAGGCUUUCCACCAGGCACACCCCAUUCUUUCCAUCACAGUGCUUUUUAAAGGACUUUAUCAUUUGUUCUCUGGGUUCAUUUAACUCUUAACUUACACCGAUUUAGCAUCUUUGCUAUAUUUCCUUUCUUAUUUCAUUCUUUAUAUGUUAUGUUACAUUUCUGUUUGAGUCUUUACAGUAUCUUCUUUCUUACCAACUUGUCUUUCUAGAAUAUUUUCACAAUUAAUGUUUUGGUUUGCUUUGAGGUAGGCGAUCAGCAGGACUUGUUUUCUGAGCACUGGUCAGGACCCUGUCUAUCUAAAUGAUAUGUAGCAAAGAAACUGGCCAAAGCCAUGUAGGACCAGCAAUUAUAAUGCACUUGCGUAAGACACUUCUACCACUACCAUGACAGUUUACAAAUGCCAUGGCAAUGACCUGGAAGUUACCUUAUAUAAUUCUGGGAACUCUCUUCCCUUUUUCCAUAAAGUUUGUGAAUAACCCAUCCCUUAUUUAGCAAAUAAUUAAGAAUGGGUAUAAAUAUAGGUAGCCAGCAAUCCACAAGUGCUACUCUGGACCAAUCUGCCUCUGGGGUGGCCCUGCUCUGUCUAUGGAGCAGUCACUUGGCUGUACACUGUUGCUCAAAUAAACUUGCUUUCUUUCAUUGUCAAAAAAAAAAAAAUAAAUAAAAAAAUAAAAAGAAAGAGGGUUUAAUUGACUCACAGUUCUGCAUGGCUUGGGAGGGCUCAGGAAACUUACAAUCUUGGUGGAAGGGGAAGAGGCACAUCUUGCAUGGCAGCAGGUGAAAGAGAGUGAGCAAGAGUAGGGAAAACUGCCUUAUAAAACCAUCAGAUCUCAUGAGCACUCACUAUCAUGAGAACAGGGUAAGGGAAAAUGACUCCAUGAUCCAGUCACCUCCCACCGGGUCCCUCCCUUGACAUGUGGGGAUUAUGAGGAUUACAAUUUGAGAUGGGAUUUGGGUGGGGACACAGAGCCAAACCAUAUCAGCAGGAUUGAAAGGUAAAGUGUGAAUAUGAUAGUUUGGAGAACUGGGACAAUAUGUGGAGAUAAUACUUAUAAGUCAUAGUCAUGAUCAUGAGUCAGAGAGAGUCAUGUGAAUGAGAUAGUGUGUUAGACUGUGUGUGUGUGUGUGUGUGUGAGAGAGAGAGAGAGAGAGAGAGAGAAGUUGGGGUAGGGGCAUGUCAUGUUUUAGGAUGGGUAUUUGGAAUAUCAUUUGGAUAUGAGUAACAAGGACCUAAAAAUGAGUUGCUUAAAAUAAUUAGGGGAUAUCUUUUCCUUACCUGAAACAAGCCCAGGACCUCCACAAUUUUAUCAAUGUCUCAGUCCCCUUAUAUAUUUUUUUGUUCCUUGGUCCUUGGUAUAUAGCUCUCAUCUUCCAGGUACCUUCUGGUUGAAGGAUGCCUGCUGCAACUCUGGCCAUCAUUUCUAUGUUUCAGGUAGAAAGAAUGAGGAAGAGGAGAGGGCAAAAAUACCUUGUCAGUGGAAUUAGUCUCCUUAUACAGAGCUUUCCCAAAAAUCCUAUCCAGUUACUGCCAAAUACAUCUCAUGGGAAAGAACUGUGACACAUAGCCACCACUAUCUGUAGCUGAGAGAACAUGGUAAGAAAAAACAGUUUCUUAGUAAGGAAAAGGAGAUGUUGGUAGGAUAUCACCAGUAGAGAAGGAGAGGUUGAAGAUUUGCGAGAGGGAGUAUAAUUAAUAGAUGAAAAUCACGAUGGUGCUAGAUACAGAUGGGAUAUGACUGGCAGAGUUUGAGAUGCUGGAGGAUAUCAUGGUAAGCAAAAAUAGACAUAUUGUCUCUGCCCUCAUGAAGCUACUGUCUUGUGAAGAAGACAGUAAUCGCAGACUCAAAUAUUUGUGAAGUUGUCACUCUGGUAAGUGCUAUGGAGGGGAAGUACAUGGUUCUGUGAAUAGGUUAAAAGAGGGCUUUACCUAAUCAGGGAAGUAAAAGCAGGGAGGAAGUAAUGAUGGAGAUGAAACCAGAAGACAGAUUCAGAAUUGAUUGGUUGAAGGAUCUGUGGAUGGGAUGGGGUAAAAGUGUUUCCAGAAGAGGAAACAGCAUGAACAAAGGGACUUAUGCUCUGUUGUCUUUUAAAAUGUAUUUUAUUUCACUUAGAAUCUUUUCCAUUAUGUCUUCAAGUUCACUAAUCUUUAGUAAUUAAUAUCAUCUAGCAUUUUUUUCUUCUCAAAUAUUACAGUUUUUAUAUCUAGAUAUAUGACUUGGACCUUAUUAAAUAGAUCUCAUGUUUUUACUUAACAUGACCAUUCUUUCCUCUAAGUUUUUGGACACAUGGAAAUAGUUAUAAUGGCUUUUAAUGUGCUUAUCUGCUAAUUAUAACAUCUAUUAAAUAUUUAAGUUCUGGGUAAGUUUGGAUUGAUUGAUUUUUCUCCUCAAGAUGGGUCCUAUUUUUCUGCUUCUUGGUAUGCCUGGUUUUUUUUUAAUUCGAUGCCAGGCAAUGUAAAUUUUACCUUUCGGUAAAAUUUUGGUGAAAUUUUUUCUUUUGGUGCUAGAUAUUUUUAUAUUCCUACAAAGCUACCUGAGCUUUGUUCUGAAAUGCACUUCUUUGGAAACAGUUAGAUCUUUUUGAGUCUUGCUUUUAUGAUUUGUUAGGCAGGACCACAGCAGUUUUUUGCAUAAAGCUAAUUAUCCCUGACUGAUGAGGCAAGACCCCUCUGAGUAUCCCAUGCCAAUGAAUUAGGAAGUUUUCCACUUUAGCUGGUGAGAACAGCAUGGUCCCCAGACCUGUUGGAGCUUCUGGCACUUGUUCCCUUUAAUCCUUUCAGGUGACUCUUUCCCCAGCCUCAGGCAAUUUCCUUUUAUGAAUUCACUGAUCAGUACUCUGUCAAAUACUUAAUGGCAAUCCUUCAAAGAUCUCCAGUGUUCUCCCUGUGUAACUCUCUCUUUUUGGGUACUCUGCUCUGUGAACUCUAGCUACCUUGGUCUUUCUGGUCUCUCAUCUCUGUCACUCCAAUUCAAGGAAUCCCCUGGAUUCUGACUACAUUCUCCCUUGUUGCUCCACAAACUGGAACCUCUCAAGCAGUAAGUGCUCACUUCUUUUUUCCUCAUCUCUCAGGGAUUACUCUUCUUCAUUGCCUAAUGUUCAGUGUCUUCAAAAACCAUUAUUUCAUAUUUUAUGUCCAUUUUUAAGUGUUUUUUGUCAGGUUGGAGGGCAAAAUCCUGUCUCCAGCUUGCCUCUUAGGAAGUUAUAUGGUGGAGACCUGUUAGAUAAUUAUUUUCUUUUCUUUUACAGUUGUUUGACCUUCUCACUACUGCCAAGUAUCACAAAUGAGUGACAGUUAUAAUUUUUUUAUCAAAUGAGAAAAGCCUGAGAAUAAGAAAUGUAUUCAAAAUCAGGGAUUUGAGGAACAAUUUGGGUCACAGGGGAAUGUGGCCAUAUAUUACAAGGAUAACUCCUCAUGACUCUAACCACAAGGAACUUCUGAGCAUAAAGACAAGUUAGAAAAGGAGAUUAACCUUCUUUCAAAGGAUAGAUGUUUAAGGCUUGGGGUAGAUAUUCACAGGAUUGGUUCCCAGCCAGGGGGCUUCCAAGACUAUAGUAAGUGUUAGAGUAAUUGUGCUCUAAUCUCAGACAUCCUACGGGAGGAUGAAACCAUACAUAGGACAAACCCACACCCACACCCAUAGUGUGGGUCACAUGACCAUAGCUUCAGACCAAUUUCAGAGACUAUAAAUCAGCACGAAAAGGCCAUGAUGGUGAGAAAAUGUGUGAAGAGCAUUGAAGAGCCUUUGGCCAAGCUUCAGAUCUUAUUAACAUCAAAUAAUUCAUUAGCAGAGAUAAACUCUAUGAAUGUAGUGAUCAUGGAUGGUCUUUCUUUCUUUUUUUUUUUUUCUUUUCACAUUCAGUUGACUUUGUGGAUGGUCUUUCAACCAGAGUUCAAAUGUCAUUCAUUAUUGUUAAACACAUACUGAAGCCAUAGAAAUGCAGUCAGUGGAAAAAAGCCUUCAGGAACAAAUCAAACCUGAGUAAUCAUGAGAAAUUUCAACCUGGAGAGAAACUGUUGAAUAUACAAAAUGUGAUACUCCACUCUGUUCUUAUCCCAUGCAGACUCCCCCAAUCUGUGUAAGUGAUUCCUUUGGAUCCCUCCUCACAUGGCUUUGGUGAGGGAGUUGCAUGCCCCUCUCCUUCCUCAAGAAAAAGGAAAACACUCUUCCCCAAGCCAAGGACUCACAACACUGUAAAUUCUUAUCUAAUUCUUUCUAGCUUUCUGAGUACAUAUGGGCUGAAAAGGAAUGGAAUGAAUACCAGUAGCAUGACUAGUAUGCUCUCCCCAUGUAAGGCCCGUAGGAUUGUGUUCAGAUCUCCUGGGAUGUUCUUUUUAGAAUGUGGAGGCACUGGGUACCUUUUUCUUUUCUUUUCUUUUCUUUUCUUUUUAAAGGCUAUAUGGCUUUAACCAAAAUUCUGAGGAAAGUGUGAAAGUUCCAUUCAAUAACCUGCUAAAUUUAUAUUAUCUUUUCUCAUUUAAUAUUACAAUAGAAGCAUGCUUCUGCCAUUAAAAACAUCUGAAUCGGAUUUUUUAUCACUUUCAAUUUAAAGCAUAGUCUUCAAAGGUAAAUUACUAAGAAAGUAUAGAUAUUUUUUAGGCUCUAAAUAUACGUUUCUGAAUUGUUUUCUAGUAAAAGGAAUAUUUGUUUGGCUUUUCAAUAGCAAAGGACAUCCUCAGCAUUUUUUUUAAUGGAGAAAAUGAUAGUGGAAAAGAAAGUCAUAGAUUGCAUUUUUUCCUAGAUCAGGAAUUCAUAAAUAAGACUAAGAGGCAAGACACCAACCAAAAAAAGCAUUUGCAACAAGUGUGACAGAUACAAGGUUAAUAACCUUAAUGUACAAAGAAUUCUCACAGCAAAAUACAAAUGAUUAAGAAACGCUGAGAGUAUCUUCCCAUCAUUAAUAAUAAUAAUAAAUACAGUUUGAAUCAAUUAAAUGUCAUUUUGUCUGUCAAAAUGGCAAAGAUAUUUUCAAAGCAAAUGUUCAGCACUGUUAAGGGUAUGUGAGAAGUCUUCUGCAUUGCUAGUGUUGACAAAAACCUUUCUAGAAAGCAAUUUGGUAUUAUUGAAUAACGGCCUUAAAAUAGUUCAUACCCGUUUGAACUAGUAAUUCCAUUUCUAAUAAUAUACCAUAAAGAAAUAAUUGGAGGUAUGCACAGAGGUUUGUUGGGGGAAAAUCACCACAAUGAUAAUCUAGUGAACAAAAAUAAAUGGAAACAAGAUUUUUGUUAUUUGGUCAAGUAGGUAAGUUCAUAUGAUGGGAUAUUACACGUUAUCAUAAAGAAUUUUGCAAAGACUUUUUAAUGUCAUAGAAAAUGUUAUGCCAAGAUAAUUGUGAUAAAACAUUAUAUACAAAAAGAAUCUCAGAUGUAGUAUAUUAAUUACAACUGUGCAUGUAUGUGUGUGAUGUUAGACUUGGUAUGGACCAUUUUCCCAAUGUUUUUCAGAUGAUUUUUCUUUUAUAAAAUGAAAUCAGGAAAUGUCAUACUAUGUAGCUGAACUCAUAUGACUUUUCUGAGUCCAGCUAUAUAUCUAUUUUAAUUGUUGUUAAUGUUCCAUGAUUCCCAAAUUAAGUGGUUUAUGAGGUUUAUAUUGAUGCUGAACAUUGAGGACACAUAUGGCACUAAAUCAUAUCCCAGGUGUCUGAGAGCAUUCAGAUAUGUCUUGAAAUUUUCCAGUGCAAAUCAAAGAGGGACUCUAUGUCACAAGAUACCAGAAGCUCACAUGGUAAGGUCAUCUGAUGCAGUAUCAAACAAAUAUCCCCAAACUGUGCAUUGAGGUUCUACUUGCAGGCUUCCUCCCCUUGUCUCUUCUGAUAACCUUCUGCUUAUUAAUGGAAUGUGAGUUGCUGUGGUGAUGGGGGUGAGGAAUUAACUGGAAGGGAAUUGUGCAAUAUGAAGGAAGGUGUAAUCUAUUUAAGUCUGUAAGAGAUUACAAGUCACCAAGAAAGCCUGCGAUGGUGAGAAAAUGUGUGAAGAGCAUUGAAGAGCCUUUAGCCAAGCUUCAGAUCUUAUUAACAUCAAAAUUCAUUAGCAGUGAUGAACUCUAUGAAUGUAGUAAUCAUGGAUGGUCGUUCAAGCAGAGUUUGGAUGUUAUUCAUUAUUGUUAAAUACAUACUGAAGCCAUAGGAACGCAUUUGAUAUAAUCCUAAGAUGUCACUUUGCCUGCUCUUAUGAUGCAAAUUGGCACCAGAAAUCCAGCCAACUUUAUUAAAAUUGUGGAAAUCUGACUGGACUCAGAUCCAUUAAUCCUUGAAAGCAGGUAAUACAUGUAUUUUUGCCAUCAUUAUUUCUCCAGCACUUAUCACAAUGUGUAGCACUUUACUAGGUAUACUUUUAAAAUGUUUUAAAAUUCUUAUACAUAUAUAAAUAAAGAAGAUAAAAUCAAGUUGACUCAAGUCUAGAAAACAUGGAUGAGGGAUUUAAGAAUUCUAAAGUGUUUAUUCUGAGGCACCAUAUUGCUUUAUGUUUGGAGGCUCAGUGUAUAUUAUCAAUGUAGAGGCUUCAAGAGGGACCCAUUAUUUCAUAUGGUUAUUCUAUCCUUUACUUAGGGGUGUUAUAAUCUCAUGCUAUGAUUUUGUUUUUAUUAUAUUUUGCUUUAAAGUACUAUGUCUGAUAUUAAUACAUCAUCUUUUUAUUAUUUGCAUGUAAUAACUUAUUCCAUCCAUUUAUUUUCAUCUUUGCUGUAUCUUUAUGUUUAAGAUAUUUCUCUUGUUAAUUGCAUGUAGCUGCCUUUAUAAUGGAAAGAUACAUAAAUUUCCUUUAAUUACAGCAUCCUCAAAUAUUCUGUAAUUGGAGAUUUGAUUUCCUCUUUGAAGGAAAGCUUCAUUUAUUCCUUCUCCAGUGCUCUCCCUUUCUUUAUGUACUUCCAAGUUUCUGCCCUAUAUCAUUUUCUUUCUGCCCGAAGAAAAUCUUCUAAUAUUUCUUGCAGGGCAGGUCUGUUGGUGAUCAAUUCAUUCUGUUUUUGUUCAUCUGAGAAUGUCUUUAUUUCUCCUUUACUUUUUUUUUCUUCUCCUUUACUUUUGAAAGAUCUUUUCCUAUAUGUAGAAAUCUAGGGUGGUAGUCAUUUUUCUUUUAACACUUUAAAUAUUUCACUUUACUCUUGUUGCUUGCAUGGUUUCUGAUGAAAGCUGCUAGAAUUAUUAUUCUUAUUCUAUUAUAAGUAAGAUAUUUGGUGUUCUCUGAGCUUCCUGGAUCUGUAAUUUGGUGUCUGUCAUUAAUUUUGGAAAAUUCUUAGCCAUUAUUACUUGAUAUUUCUUCUGCUGUAUUCUCUUUCUCUUCUCCAUCUGAUGUUCCAGUUAUGCAUAUGUGACUCCAGAUUUGCCUAUCCAUCAAGAUUUUAGGGUGAUGAUUUGCCCUGAAAUUUCAUUUCUCUGACAGGUCCAAAAAAGUGAUUGAUUUUUAGUUUGUCCAGGUUUUUUUUCUGGUUGUUGGUGCCUCCAGCCUCACAUUGAUUCUGUGGUGGAAGAAAAGCAUGGGGAAGCAAAGAGUCAGUAGAUAUUGUGGGUUCCUUAAAAAGGAGGAACCAUAAGCCCCAUAUUUUAGGGAUGGGAAGAAAUGCCAGGUAGGUUUGCAAGAUCCUUAAGCAAUGUGUUCUUUUGUCUCACCUUCUGGCUAAGGCCAGAGAGGACAAGACUACAAAAUAGAAUUGUCUGCGUGGUGUCUAUAAUUAUUUGGAGCCUCUUCAUGUGGUUUCCCUCAGCUCAGGGUAUUUACAGGAGUAUAUGUGAGACAAAGACAGCCUCACGGAGGUUAAUAGACCUCAGCAUAUCAUAGGAACAGUAGAAUGUUUUCCAUGUAUAUGAGUGAUAUAUGAUACCCAAAGAGAUAGUUGGACCCAAAGCAGCUUUACAGUAAAGAAGGAAGCUCACUCAACAGCUACCUGCUUGGACAGACAUUGAUGAACAAAUAUGACAUGUAUGCCAGCAUGGAUACAUGAUACCCAACAUAUGUUACCCAUCCUGAUGUUUUGACACUAUUUAACAUCCCUAGAACUUAAAUACAACCCCAAAGCAGAGAGUGAGAGGGGGACUCCAUACUGCUGGAGAUUAAGUUUCCACCACUCAGUAGAAUGGGAACUUGACAUAUAAUUUAUGUUGAGUUGCAGAGAAAAUAACUUACAUUUCCUGCAUACCGGAGUUUGUCAGAUAAUACCCAUACCUGCAGAAUAAUCAUUAACAGAAAGUGGGUGAUAAACACUGAGUAUCUCAAACAAAUUUAUCUACUCAAAACAUGGGGUAUGUGGCUCUUAUAGUAGAAAACCACGGUGGUCUUAUCUCAAGGCCAGAGUGAGAUGUGAGAAAUGACCUCUGGCAUUUUGGUGGGUACCAACAUAAAGAGAACAGGGAAUCUGAGGAGAGCAAAGGACAACUUCUCUGCAGAACGAAAUCACUGUCAUUGGUGAGGUGUGAUUCUACUUCAUUUCUUCAUCUUCCUGUCCCUGUCCCUCUUACUUCAAAUACUUCUCUUUUCUCCCUGGUUAUUUCCUCUACUCCCUCCUUCCUCUUUUUUAUCCCUCUCCUUGUUUAUUUUUCAUCCCUCCUUAUCUAUUCCUUAACCUCUUGUCUUAGUCAGUUCGGGCUGCUGUAACUGACUACCAUAGACUGGGUGGCUUAAACAAUAGAAAUAUACUUCUCACCAUUCUGGAGGCUGGGAAGUCCAAGACAAAGGCACUGGCAGAUCUGCUGUCUGUUGAGGGCCCUCUUUUUCCUGGUUUGCAGAUAGCCAUCUUCUCGUUGUGUCCUCACAAGGUGGAGAGCAGACCGAGGAAGCAAGCUUUCUCCCUUCUCUUCUUAUAAGGUCAUUAAUCUCAUUAUGAGGGCUCUACCCAUAUGACCUUAUUACCUCCCAAAGUCCCCAUCUCCAAUACAGUCACACUGAGGAUUUAGGUUUCAACAUCUGAAUUUGGUGGGGCCACAAACAUUUUGUCCAUACCACCCCUCUAUCUACUCCUGCCUCCCUCUCAUGCUCUUCCACCUUACAUCCUCUUCUCUUUCCUCUUGCUUUUUCUUUUUCUUUUCUUUUCUUUUUUUUUUUGAGAUGGAGUUUCGCUCUCGUUGCCCAGGCUGGAGUGCAAUGGUAAGAUCUUGGCUCACUGCAACCUCCGCCUCCUGGGUAGAAGCGAUAUUCCUGCCUCAGCCUCCUGAGUAGCUGGGAUUACAGGCACUUGCCACCAUGACCAGCUAAUUUUUUGUAUUUUCAGUAGAGACGGGGUUUCACCAUGUUGGCCAGGCUGGUCUCGAACUCCUGACCUCAGGUGAUCUACCUGCCUCAGCCUCCCAAAGUGCUGGGAUUACAGGCAUGAACCAUUGCACCUGGCCUCCUCUUGCUUUUUCUACUUCAACUUAGUAUCUGUUCUUUCUCCAUUAUCUUAUUUUUCCUUAUCUUCCUAAUUCCAUUUACUUCCAGCUGCUAUUUUCAUUCAUCUUUUCUUAUUCCUAUUAUAUUCUUUCUUCUUUUCUUCUUCCCUCUCUUCCUCCUCAAUUCCUUUCUUUCCUACUUGACCUUCUUUCUCAUUUCUCCCACUCUUCAUGCUCCCAUCUAACAAGAUAGUGGAAAAGAGAGAAAAAGGUAAUAGAAUGCAAUAAAAAUGUACUUAAAAUGGUAACAGGAAUAGGUGAUGGGUUUGACUGGGGAAUAAGGCAGAGAGAGGCAUUAUGAAUAACCCAAAGUAAAAUAGGGAGAAAAAGAGGCUAUUAAAUAUGAUUUUUUAAAACUACUUAUCAAAAAGCCAUAAUUAUUCUGAUAGGCAAAAUGGUAAAGUCACUUCAGGAAAAAGAAAGGGAUGUUACUUAUUUAGAUUAUUACUCAGUAUUGCUCUUGAUGUUUUAGCAACUCAGAGAAGACCACCAAAUAAGUGCUAUUCAUAUUGUAAAAGAAGUGAUCAAAUUAUUUCUUUUUCUUAUAGUGUGAUUGUACAUUAAGAAAUCACAAUAGAUUUUUAAAAAAAUAAAAUACUAGAAUUGAGGACUUCUACUUCCAGAAAGAAGUAGUAAACAGGGUAGAUGUAUUUUCCCUAUUCAUCUCUGGAAAAAAUAUAUAAACAAAACAUAAGAAGACCCAGAAAGUUGAAAAGAAGAUGAUGUAUUCUCUAGGGAACUUGGAACCAAGGAAUCAACAUGGAGAUAUGCACUAAACCUUCACCUGGCAUCAGACUUAAUGGUGAGAGACUGAAUUUCUCCUUGCCAUCAGGAACAAGCCCCCAGGCUCCGCUCUUGCCAGAGGGACAGGAGCCAUGGCUCAGAAAAUGGACUGUGGUGCGGGCCUCCUCGGCUUCCAGGCUGAGGCCUCCGUAGAAGACAGCGCCUUGCUUAUGCAGACCUUGAUGGAGGCCAUCCAGAUCUCAGAGGCUCCACCUACUAACCAGGCCACCGCAGCUGCUAGUCCCCAGAGUUCACAGCCCCCAACUGCCAAUGAGAUGGCUGACAUUCAGGUUUCAGCAGCUGCCGCUAGGCCUAAGUCAGCCUUUAAAGUCCAGAAUGCCACCACAAAAGGCCCAAAUGGUGUCUAUGAUUUCUCUCAGGCUCAUAAUGCCAAGGAUGUGCCCAACACGCAGCCCAAGGCAGCCUUUAAGUCCCAAAAUGCUACCCCAAAGGGUCCAAAUGCUGCCUAUGAUUUUUCCCAGGCAGCAACCACUGGUGAGUUAGCUGCUAACAAGUCUGAGAUGGCCUUCAAGGCCCAGAAUGCCACUACUAAAGUGGGCCCAAAUGCCACCUACAAUUUCUCUCAGUCUCUCAAUGCCAAUGACCUGGCCAACAGCAGGCCUAAGACCCCUUUCAAGGCUUGGAAUGAUACCACUAAGGCCCCAACAGCUGAUACCCAGACCCAGAAUGUAAAUCAGGCCAAAAUGGCCACUUCCCAGGCUGACAUAGAGACCGACCCAGGUAUCUCUGAACCUGACGGUGCAACUGCACAGACAUCAGCAGAUGGUUCCCAGGCUCAGAAUCUGGAGUCCCGGACAAUAAUUCGGGGCAAGAGGACCCGCAAGAUUAAUAACUUGAAUGUUGAAGAGAACAGCAGUGGGGAUCAGAGGCGGGCCCCACUGGCUGCAGGGACCUGGAGGUCUGCACCAGUUCCAGUGACCACUCAGAACCCACCUGGCGCACCCCCCAAUGUGCUCUGGCAGACGCCAUUGGCUUGGCAGAACCCCUCAGGCUGGCAAAACCAGACAGCCAGGCAGACCCCACCAGCACGUCAGAGCCCUCCAGCUAGGCAGACCCCACCAGCCUGGCAGAACCCAGUCGCUUGGCAGAACCCAGUGAUUUGGCCAAACCCAGUAAUCUGGCAGAACCCAGUGAUCUGGCCAAACCCCAUUGUCUGGCCCGGCCCUGUUGUCUGGCCGAAUCCACUGGCCUGGCAGAAUCCACCUGGAUGGCAGACUCCACCUGGAUGGCAGACCCCACCGGGCUGGCAGGGUCCUCCAGACUGGCAAGGUCCUCCUGACUGGCCGCUACCACCCGACUGGCCACUGCCACCUGAUUGGCCACUUCCCACUGACUGGCCACUACCACCUGACUGGAUCCCCGCUGAUUGGCCAAUUCCACCUGACUGGCAGAACCUGCGCCCCUCGCCUAACCUGCGCCCUUCUCCCAACUCGCGUGCCUCACAGAACCCAGGUGCUGCACAGCCCCGAGAUGUGGCCCUUCUUCAGGAAAGAGCAAAUAAGUUGGUCAAGUACUUGAUGCUUAAGGACUACACAAAGGUGCCCAUCAAGCGCUCAGAAAUGCUGAGAGAUAUCAUCCGUGAAUACACUGAUGUUUAUCCAGAAAUCAUUGAACGUGCAUGCUUUGUCCUAGAGAAGAAAUUUGGGAUUCAACUGAAAGAAAUUGACAAAGAAGAACACCUGUAUAUUCUCAUCAGUACCCCCGAGUCCCUGGCUGGCAUACUGGGAACGACCAAAGACACACCCAAGCUCGGUCUCCUCUUGGUGAUUCUGGGUGUCAUCUUCAUGAAUGGCAACCGUGCCAGUGAGGCUGUCCUCUGGGAGGCACUACGCAAGAUGGGACUGCGUCCUGGGGUGAGACAUCCCCUCCUUGGAGAUCUAAGGAAACUUCUCACCUAUGAGUUUGUAAAGCAGAAAUACCUGGACUACAGACGAGUGCCCAACAGCAACCCCCCGGAGUAUGAGUUCCUCUGGGGCCUCCGUUCCUACCAUGAGACUAGCAAGAUGAAAGUGCUGAGAUUCAUUGCAGAGGUUCAGAAAAGAGACCCUCGUGACUGGACUGCACAGUUCAUGGAGGCUGCAGAUGAGGCCUUGGAUGCUCUGGAUGCUGCUGCAGCUGAGGCCGAAGCCCGGGCUGAAGCAAGAACCCGCAUGGGAAUUGGAGAUGAGGCUGUGUCUGGGCCCUGGAGCUGGGAUGACAUUGAGUUUGAGCUGCUGACCUGGGAUGAGGAAGGAGAUUUUGGAGAUCCCUGGUCCAGAAUUCCAUUUACCUUCUGGGCCAGAUACCACCAGAAUGCCCGCUCCAGAUUCCCUCAGACCUUUGCCGGUCCCAUUAUUGGUCCUGGUGGUACAGCCAGUGCCAACUUCGCUGCCAACUUUGGUGCCAUUGGUUUCUUCUGGGUUGAGUGAGAUGUUGGAUAUUGCUAUCAAUCGCAGUAGUCUUUCCCCUGUGUGAGGCUGAAGCCUCAGAUUCCUUCUAAACACAGCUAUCUAGAGAGCCACAUCCUGUUGACUGAAAGUGGCAUGCAAGAUAAAUUUAUUUGCUGUUCCUUGUCUACUGCUUUUUUUCCCCUUGUGUGCUGUCAAGUUUUGGUAUCAGAAAUAAACAUUGAAAUUGCAAAGUGAA